AGACCUCCAUCAGCUCGCCGCGCAGCGCGGCUGUAUUUGCGGCCUGUGCGAGUAGGCGCUUGGGCACUCAGUCUCCCUGGCGAGCGACGGGCAGAAAUCUCGAACCAGUGGAGCGCACUCGUAACCUGGAUCCCAGAAGGUCGCGAAGGCAGUACCGUUUCCUCAGCGGCGGACGGAGUCUUACUCUGUCGUUCAGGUUGGAGUGCAGUGGCGCGACCUCGGCUCACUGCAACAUCUGCCUCCCAGGUUCAAGCAAUUCUCCUGCCUCACCUUCCAGAGUAGCUGGGAUUACAGACUGCUGCAGUAAGAAUGUCUUUUCCACCUCAUUUGAAUCGCCCUCCCAUGGGAAUCCCAGCACUCCCACCAGGGAUCCCACCCCCGCAGUUUCCAGGAUUUCCUCCACCUGUACCUCCAGGGACCCCAAUGAUUCCUGUACCAAUGAGCAUUAUGGCUCCUGCUCCAACUGUCUUAGUACCCACUGUGUCUAUGGUUGGAAAGCAUUUGGGCGCAAGAAAGGAUCAUCCAGGCUUAAAGGCUAAAGAAAAUGAUGAAAAUUGUGGUCCUACUACCACUGUUUUUGUUGGCAACAUUUCCGAGAAAGCUUCAGACAUGCUUAUAAGACAACUCUUAGCUAAAUGUGGUUUGGUUUUGAGCUGGAAGAGAGUACAAGGUGCUUCCGGAAAGCUUCAAGCCUUCGGAUUCUGUGAGUACAAGGAGCCAGAAUCUACCCUCCGUGCACUCAGAUUAUUACAUGACCUGCAAAUUGGAGAGAAAAAGCUACUCGUUAAAGUUGAUGCAAAGACAAAGGCACAGCUGGAUGAAUGGAAAGCAAAGAAGAAAGCUUCUAAUGGGAAUGCAAGGCCAGAAACUGUCACUAAUGACGAUGAAGAAGCCUUGGAUGAAGAAACAAAGAGGAGAGAUCAGAUGAUUAAAGGGGCUAUUGAAGUUUUAAUUCGUGAAUACUCCAGUGAGCUAAAUGCCCCCUCACAGGAAUCUGAUUCUCACCCCAGGAAGAAGAAGAAGGAAAAGAAGGAGGACAUUUUCCGCAGAUUUCCAGUGGCCCCACUGAUCCCUUAUCCACUCAUCACUAAGGAGGAUAUAAAUGCUAUAGAAAUGGAAGAAGACAAAAGAGACCUGAUAUCUCGAGAGAUCAGCAAAUUCAGAGACACACAUAAGAAACUGGAAGAAGAGAAAGGCAAAAAGGAAAAAGAAAGACAGGAAAUUGAGAAAGAACGGAGAGAAAGAGAGAGGGAGCGUGAAAGGGAACGAGAAAGGCGAGAACGGGAACGAGAAAGGGAAAGAGAACGUGAACGAGAAAAGGAGAAAGAACGGGAGCGGGAACGAGAACGGGAUAGGGACCGUGACCGGACAAAAGAGAGAGACCGAGAUCGGGAUCGAGAGAGAGAUCGUGACCGGGAUAGAGAAAGGAGCUCAGAUCGUAAUAAGGAUCGCAGUCGAUCAAGAGAAAAAAGCAGAGAUCGUGAAAGGGAACGAGAGCGGGAAAGAGAGAGAGAGAGAGAACGAGAGCGAGAACGAGAACGGGAGCGAGAGAGAGAGCGAGAGAGGGAACGGGAGCGAGAAAGAGAAAAAGACAAAAAACGGGACCGAGAAGAAGAUGAAGAAGAUGCAUACGAACGAAGAAAACUUGAAAGAAAACUCCGAGAGAAAGAAGCUGCUUAUCAAGAGCGCCUUAAGAAUUGGGAAAUCAGAGAACGAAAGAAAACCCGGGAAUAUGAGAAAGAAGCUGAAAGAGAAGAAGAAAGAAGAAGAGAAAUGGCCAAAGAAGCUAAACGACUAAAAGAAUUCUUAGAAGACUAUGAUGAUGAUAGAGAUGACCCCAAAUAUUACAGAGGAAGUGCUCUUCAGAAAAGGUUGCGUGAUAGAGAAAAGGAAAUGGAAGCAGAUGAACGAGAUAGGAAGAGAGAGAAGGAGGAGCUUGAGGAAAUCAGGCAGCGCCUUCUGGCAGAAGGGCAUCCAGAUCCAGAUGCAGAGCUCCAGAGGAUGGAACAAGAGGCUGAGAGGCGCAGGCAGCCACAAAUAAAGCAAGAGCCAGAAUCAGAAGAGGAGGAAGAAGAAAAGCAAGAAAAAGAAGAAAAACGAGAAGAACCCAUGGAAGAGGAAGAGGAGCCAGAGCAAAAGCCUUGUCUGAAACCUACUCUGAGGCCCAUCAGCUCUGCUCCAUCUGUUUCCUCUGCCAGUGGCAAUGCAACACCUAACACUCCUGGGGAUGAGUCUCCCUGUGGUAUUAUUAUUCCUCAUGAAAACUCACCAGAUCAACAGCAACCUGAGGAGCAUAGGCCAAAAAUAGGACUAAGUCUUAAACUGGGUGCUUCCAAUAGUCCUGGUCAGCCUAAUUCUGUGAAGAGAAAGAAACUACCUGUAGAUAGUGUCUUUAACAAAUUUGAGGAUGAAGACAGUGAUGACGUACCCCGAAAAAGGAAACUGGUUCCCUUGGAUUAUGGUGAAGAUGAUAAAAAUGCAACCAAAGGCACUGUAAACACUGAAGAAAAGCGUAAACACAUUAAGAGUCUCAUUGAGAAAAUCCCUACAGCCAAACCUGAGCUCUUCGCUUAUCCCCUGGAUUGGUCUAUUGUGGAUUCUAUACUGAUGGAACGUCGAAUUAGACCAUGGAUUAAUAAGAAAAUCAUAGAAUAUAUAGGUGAAGAAGAAGCUACAUUAGUUGAUUUUGUUUGUUCUAAGGUUAUGGCUCAUAGUUCACCCCAGAGCAUUUUAGAUGAUGUUGCCAUGGUACUUGAUGAAGAAGCAGAAGUUUUUAUAGUCAAAAUGUGGAGAUUAUUGAUAUAUGAAACAGAAGCCAAGAAAAUUGGUCUUGUGAAGUAAAACUUUUUAUAUUUAGAGUUCCAUUUCAGAUUUCUUCUUUGCCACCCUUUUAAGGACUUUGAAUUUUUCUUUGUCUUUGAAGACAUUGUGAGAUCUGUAAUUUUUUUUUUUUGUAGAAAAUGUGAAUUUUUUGGUCCUCUAAUUUGUUGUUGCCCUGUGUACUCCCUUGGUUGUAAAGUCAUCUGAAUCCUUGGUUCUCUUUAUACUCACCAGGUACAAAUUACUGGUAUGUUUUAUAAGCCGCAGCUACUGUACACAGCCUAUCUGAUAUAAUCUUGUUCUGCUGAUUUGUUUCUUGUAAAUAUUAAAACGACUCCCCAAUUAUUUUGCAGAAUUGCACUUAAUAUUGAAAUGUACUGUAUAGGAACCAACAUGAACAAUUUUAAUUGAAAACACCAGUCAUAAACUAUUACCACCCCCACUCUCUUUUGAUCAGAAAUGGCAAGCCCUUGUGAAGGCAUGGAGUUUAAAAUUGGAAUGCAAAAAUUAGCAGACAAUCCAUUCCUACUGUAUUUCUGUAUGAAUGUGUUUGUGAAUGUAUGUGUAAAAGUCUUUCUUUUCCCUAAUUUGCUUUGGUGGGGUCCUUAAAACAUUUCCCAACUAAAGAAUAGAAUUGUAAAGGAAAAGUGGUACUGUUCCAACCUGAAAUGUCUGUUAUAAUUAGGUUAUUAGUUUCCCAGAGCAUGGUGUUCUCGUGUCGUGAGCAAUGUGGUUUGCUAACUGGAUGGGGUUUUCUUAUUAAUAAGAUGGCUGCUUCAGCUUCUCUUUUAAAGGAAUGUGGAUCAUAGUGAUUUUUCCUUUUAAUUUUAUUGCUCAGAAAUGAGGCAUAUCCUAAAAAUCCUGGAGAGCUGUAUUUAAUGCAUUUUUGCACUAAUUGGUCCUUAGUUUAAUUCUAUUGUAUCUGUUUAUUUAACAAAAAAUUCAUCAUACCAAAAAGUGUAAGUGAAAACCCCCUUUAAAACAAAACAAAAAAAUGAAAUAAAAUUAGGCAAAUUGACAGACAGUGAGAGUUUUACAAACAUGAUAGGUAUUCUGCUCGGCAAUUUGUAAGUUUACAUGUUAUUUAAGGAUAAAGGUAAAUCAUUCAAGGCAGUUACCAACCACUAACUAUUUGUUUUCAUUUUUGUCUUGUAGAAGGUUUAUAUCUUGUUUUACCUUGGCUCAUUAGUGUUUAAAAAUGUACUGAUGAUGUGCUUAGAGAAAUUCCUGGGGCUUUCUUCGUUGUAGAUCAGAAUUUCACCAGGGAGUAAAAUUACCUGAAAACGUAAGAAGUUUUAAACAGCUUUUCACACAAAUUAGAUGCAACUGUUCCCAUGUCUGAGUACUUAUUUAAAAGAAAGGUAAAGAUUGGCCUGUUAGAAAAAGCAUAAUGUGAGCUUUGGAUUACUGGAUUUUUUUUUUUUUUAAACACACCUGGAGAGGACAUUUGAAAACACUGUUCUUACCCUCGAACCCUGAUGUGGUUCCAUUAUGUAAAUAUUUCAAAUAUUAAAAAUGUAUAUAUUUGAUCCUGGGGACUCAUAUUCUUUCAGAAUCAUGUAAAUAAAUGGCAUCAUGUUGUAAUUGUGUGGUGCAUACUAGAAAAGUUAAAAAUAUGGGCUGAACUUUUUAUGGACUUGAUUUUUAUGACUAUUGGUAUCUAAAGGUCAAGGAAGCCAUUUACAUUAUUUUGGAUGAAUCUACUAUACAUCUAUGGAAAUGUCUCUUUUAUUUUAAAUUCUGGUUUCUCAACGGAAAAUUUCAGAAAAGAUGCCCCUUGCCAUUUUCGUUAAUUUUUCAGUCUUUUCUUAGACACACCCCCAGCCUAAGACCUUGUUCGAGGAGUUUAUUGUGUCUGUCUUUUCUUAACAUACUGCACUGUUCUUAAGCAUCAUAUUGUGUUGUUUUUAUUUAGCCACUAUUAACAUGAAGGUUUAUUCAGGUAGAUUUGAUUUCCUUUGCUUCGUUUCUUCUCCUGCUCUGUCAACUGUACUUAUCUUAAAGGGCCACUCUAAAAACAAGGGAGAUGUCGUAAUCUGAAACCUUUGGGGAGAUGUACUCUGUACUGCAUAACAUCUCCAGUGAGGUUUGUGACAGGACCUCAACUAAAUAUAUGAAUUUGUGCAAGUUCAUAUAUUAAAGUUUCUGCAGCAGAGUGAAAAUUGUUACAGUAAAUGUGGUAGAAACUGUUAAUCGCUUAAUGCCAGUUUAAAUCAUGUUUUGUAACCAAGCUUCAGUAAAAGGCUUUAGAUUGUCAGAGUUGGUUGAUUUUUAGAAUUGUAUAUAUAAAGAAUUAGACAUUAAACAGGCAUAUUCUAGUGUCUGAAAAUACACAUAAGAAAUUUCUAUUAAGUUGCUUGAACUUUGUGGGUUAAUUUUACCAUAAUCUCAUAAAUUAAUUUUAGUUUGAAAACCUUAUACAGUAUGAAUUCAUUUUGCCAUUUCAAGUUGUUAUAUAAAGAGCAUGAAAGUCUUUUUUUGUUGUUUUUUUGGGGUUUUUUUUUUUUUGAGAGGAAGUUGUGCUUUUGUCGCCCAGGAUGGAGUGCAAUGGCGCGAGCUCAGCUCACUUCAACUUCCGCCUCCCGGGUUCUGGAGAUAUUCUGCUUCAGUUUUCUGAGUAGCUGGGAUUACAGGUGCCCACCACGACACCUGGCUAAUUUUUUGUAUUUUUAGUAGAGACAGGAUUUCACCUUGUUGGCCAGGCUGGUCUCAAACUCCUGACCUCAGGUGAUCCACCCGCCUCAGCCUCCCAAAGUGCUGGUAUUACAGGCGUGAGCCACCUUGCCUGGCCAAAGCGUGAACAUCUUAAGAACCAGUCUUGAUCUGGCAAAAAAGUAGUAGAAUACUACUUUUCUUUAUUUGUCCCUAAAAAUAAAGUAUGUACAUCUGUUCACAAGGAAGAAAGGUAAGUUUGAAGUUGUUUUUCUUAAACUUUAAUGUGACCCCAAAUCAUCUGAGGAGUGCUUGUAGAAAUAGAGACACUGAAGUAGCAGCGCUGGGGUGGCGCCGCAGGCUUUGCAUUUCUGGACAGCUCCCAGCUAAUGUCAUUGCCAACUGAUCCAAGACUACAUUUUGAUUAGCACUUUAAGGUGUCUAUUCAGUAUUAUUUUAUCCUAACAGACUACAUAAAUGCAGCUGAAUUUUCCUUUAAGUAGAUUUUAAAGAGAAAAACAUUUUUUGAGGCAAAUACACGUAACUCAUGAACGUAAUGUAAUCUUGCAAAAUUAUGUCUGAGAAAGCCCUAAUAUUCUAGGCUUUUUUUCCAUCCAGCCCUGAAAAUUUUUUCUGUAGAUAACUUUAUGUUGUAACUUAUUCUGAAUCUUAUUAUGGCAUUUCCCUGUAAACUAUGUAAGUGUAAGCUAAUGAUUAUUUUGUGAAGCGUGCUGUUUCAGGUAUUAAUCUGCCAUGAAUACUAGAUAUAGUAGAAAAACUGAGAAAACAUUUAGCUUGAGAGCCAAUUUGAACUAGACACUAUCUUUUUUUCUCCUUUUUAAUGGAAUAAAUUUAAUGCAAAUAAGUGUAAGCAGGUAUACAAUGUUUAGAUGAGGCUUAUUUUCCCAACUCUUUUUAACAGGUUUUAUGAUAUCCCCAAUUUAUACCCAAAAGACUGCUGAGAGGUUUUAUGUCAAAUUGAUUACAAACUUCUCUGGGUUGUAUUUCAGUCUUCUGUUAAGUAUGAAAUUGAGAAAUAGUUUUGCUCAACAAAAGAUGAUGAGGGAUUGAUUUGUGAAUGUCACUGGAGAUAAAAGGGUAUGAGAAGGAAUCCCAAGCAGGCAAAGAAACAGUCUAGCUGUCAAGAAGAAAACAGGGAGAUACAUACCAAACCCAGGAGCUACUAAUAUAACAAUCAUACUAUAGAGCGAAGUGAACUUACACUUUUUGAUAAACUGAUAGAUUUUUUGUAAUGUGAUUAUGGUAAAAUACUGAAAUAUUUAUGUUAAUUUAUUUGCAUUUGAAUGCUUACAUUUUUAAUUGACAGAAUCUUUGCAUUUCAUUACUUGAGUCAUGAAGGCGAAAUUAAAGAAUGGCAGUCUAAAAUACCCAGGUAAAGAAGAUAAUUUCUAGAAACAAAAAUAAAAAUUCUUUUCAAGCCAUGUUGUUUGAAUUAAAUGACA